GCAGAACUGCUAGCUGCGGGGGAGAGGGCAGGGGUCGGGCGCCUGUGGCGGAGCCGGGCUGGGGCCAGGGCAGGGAGGCUGACAAGCGGCGGGAGAAGCCGGCGGAGGGCGGGAUCGCGCCUCCUGACAUGUUGGGGGUAUCCCUGGCCGGGCCGGGCCGGGGCUAAGAGCGGCGCUGCGGGCCGGGGUCGGGGUCGGGUCGCGGUCCGCCCCCGCUGUCCCUCCGUCCUGCCCUGUCGAGGACGUGCGUUCCGCACUCGGCCGCCUCCAGAGGGAGCGAGGGAAGCGGCUAGAGGAUCGGGGAGAAGGAGCAUUCGCCGGAGGCUGGAGGAGGCUGACCCGCGUCCCCGCCCAGCCUGCUCCUAUGCGGUACUUGAAGGAUGGCGAAGAGGUCGCGCAGUGAGGAUGAGGAUGAUGACCUUCAGUAUGCCGAUCAUGAUUAUGAAGUACCACAACAAAAAGGACUGAAGAAACUCUGGAACAGAGUAAAAUGGACAAGGGACGAGGAUGAUAAAUUAAAGAAGUUGGUUGAACAACAUGGAACUGAUGAUUGGACUCUAAUUGCUAGUCAUCUUCAAAAUCGCUCUGAUUUUCAGUGCCAGCAUCGAUGGCAGAAAGUUUUAAAUCCUGAAUUGAUAAAGGGUCCUUGGACUAAAGAAGAAGAUCAGAGGGUUAUUGAAUUAGUUCAGAAAUAUGGGCCAAAAAGAUGGUCUUUAAUUGCAAAACAUUUAAAAGGAAGAAUAGGCAAGCAGUGUAGAGAAAGAUGGCAUAAUCAUCUGAAUCCUGAGGUAAAGAAAUCUUCCUGGACAGAAGAGGAGGACAGGAUCAUCUAUGAAGCACAUAAGCGGUUGGGAAAUCGUUGGGCAGAAAUUGCCAAACUACUUCCAGGAAGGACUGAUAAUUCUAUCAAAAAUCAUUGGAAUUCUACUAUGCGAAGAAAAGUGGAACAGGAGGGCUAUUUACAAGAUGGAAUAAAAUCAGAACGAUCUUCAUCUAAACUUCAACACAAACCUUGUGCAGCUAUGGAUCAUAUGCAAACCCAGAAUCAGUUUUACAUACCUGUUCAGAUCCCUGGGUAUCAGUAUGUGUCACCUGAAGGCAAUUGUAUAGAACAUGUUCAGCCUACUUCUGCCUUUAUUCAGCAACCCUUCAUUGAUGAAGAUCCUGAUAAGGAAAAGAAAAUAAAGGAACUUGAGAUGCUUCUUAUGUCAGCUGAGAAUGAAGUUAGAAGAAAGCGAAUUCCAUCACAGCCUGGAAGUUUUUCUAGCUGGUCUGGUAGUUUCCUCAUGGAUGAUAACAUGUCUAAUACUCUAAAUAGCCUUGACGAGCACACUAGUGAGUUUUACAGUAUGGAUGAAAAUCAGCCUGUGUCUGCUCAGCAGAAUUCACCCACAAAGUUCCUGGCCGUGGAGGCAAACGCUGUGUUAUCCUCUUUGCAGACCAUCCCAGAAUUUGCAGAGACUCUAGAACUUAUUGAAUCUUUUAAUUUAUUGCAGGAUCCUGUAGCAUGGAGUGACGUUACCAGUUUUGAUAUUUCUGAUGCUGCUGCUUCUCCUAUCAAAUCCACCCCAGUUAAAUUAAUGAGAAUUCAGCACAAUGAAGGAGCCAUGGAAUGCCAAUUUAACGUCAGUCUUGUACUUGAAGGGAAAAAAAACACUUGUAAUGGUGGCAACAGUGAAGCUGUUCCUUUAACAUCCCCAAAUAUAGCCAAGUUUAGCACUCCACCAGCCAUCCUCAGAAAGAAGAGAAAAAUGCGAGUGGGUCAUUCCCCAGGCAGCGAACUUAGGGAUGGCUCAUUGAACGAUGGUGGUAAUAUGGCGCUAAAACAUACACCACUGAAAACACUACCAUUUUCUCCUUCACAGUUUUUCAACACAUGUCCUGGUAAUGAACAACUUAAUAUAGAAAAUCCUUCAUUUACAUCAACCCCUAUUUGUGGGCAGAAAGCUCUCAUUACAACUCCUCUUCAUAAGGAAACAACUCCCAAAGAUCAAAAGGAAAAUGUAGGGUUUAGAACACCUACUAUUAGAAGAUCUAUACUGGGUACCACACCAAGAACUCCUACUCCUUUUAAGAAUGCGCUUGCUGCUCAGGAGAAAAAAUAUGGACCUCUUAAAAUUGUGUCCCAGCCACUUGCUUUCUUGGAAGAAGAUAUUCGGGAAGUUUUAAAAGAAGAAACUGGAACAGACCUAUUCCUCAAAGAGGAAGAUGAACCUGCUUACAAAAGCUGCAAACAAGAGAAUACCGCUUCUGGGAAGAAAGUCAGAAAAUCACUAGUCUUAGAUAAUUGGGAAAAAGAAGAAUCAGGCACUCAACUGUUGACUGAAGACAUUUCAGACAUGCAGUCAGAAAAUAGAUUUACUACAUCCUUAUUAAUGAUACCAUUAUUGGAAAUACAUGACAAUAGGUGCAACUUGAUUCCUGAAAAACAAGAUAUAAAUUCAACCAACAAAACAUAUACACUUACUAAAAAGAAACCAAACCCUAACACUUCCAAAGUUGUCAAAUUGGAAAAGAAUCUUCAGUCAAAUUGUGAAUGGGAAACAGUGGUUUAUGGGAAGACAGAAGACCAACUUAUUAUGACUGAACAAGCAAGAAGAUAUCUGAGUACUUACACAGCUACCAGUAGUACUUCAAGAGCUCUCAUACUGUAAUUGUUAUUAAAAUUGAUGAAAUGCCCCACUCCCUUACUGCAGUCUCUACUAAAUUAGGUUGCAGUGAAAUUUUUCUCAAUUAGUUGUUUUUAAAGUUGUAAGAUAGCCCUUUUAAUACAGCAUCUUUUUUCUAUUCUAUAUAGUAGGCAGAAAGCUAGUAAGUCACUUAAGGGGUAGAUAGUUUCAUAGUUUAUUUUUUAAGAGAUGAGAUUUUUAAAAAUUGUUUUUAAAGAACAAGAUGGGAAAAUAAUAGAAUGUUCAUGGAUUUCUAAAAGUAAAUUCUCAUAUAUUUUCUUCACAAGAUAUAUGUUGCUACUCUCUUGAUGCUGCAGUUUUGUUAUAGAUAGGUGUAUGAGUAUAUAUGAUUUCUGAAAUUAGUCUAUGUAUGGAAAGCACACAUGAUUUUAUGAAGUACUUUUGCCCAUGUGCUGAUUUACUUAGGCUACCAUUUACAAAGAAACACAUUGAAAAGGAAUUUAAAGGAAGGAUAGAAAGUUGCACUACUAAUUUUUUGUUUUUUUUUUCAGAAGCAGUAAAAUUAACUACAGUGUUAAAUGUAUUUAUUUGAGCAUAGUACUGAAAACAAAAAGCAUUCAAAAAAGAGUUUUUUCUUUAUUAGUAAAUAGUAUUUUCUUAAUCUCAGAGGAGCUGAGAGUUUUGUUGAAUGUAUUGUACAGUAUGUAGGAGCAGGAGAACUUUGUAAAUUGGAAAGAAGUCUGUUUUUAUAAUUUAUUUUUAUUUUUAAAGCUUAAAUGUAGAUAUUUAUACGUAUACAGGGUGCCUAGAAGCCAAUGUUGUUUCCUGUUAUUACAGCUAACACAGUAAAGAAUAAUUUUGACUUUAAGUAUGAAACAGUAGUAAGUUAUAGCUGCAAAGAAUACAAUAUCUAUACUGUAUGUCACAUCUACCUAAAUGUUGCACUAUGCCCUUUAAAUCAUGCUGGUUAUAAAGUAGUUCUAAAAAUGUACUAAAUAAUAAUUUAAUAUUUUCUUUUUAAAUUAUAUCGGGGGUGGUCAUAUACAUUAAUCUGGUGAUUUGUAUAUGUGUUUGAAAUUUUUGCAUUUUGUUUAAAAAAUAAUAUGGUACCUUGGUCCCUAAAAACAGUCUGCACUUAGAAGUUUAUAUUUACUCAGUGUUUCAGAAGUGGAGAACAUUAUCUUUUAUUUAUAAAAAUAUUUUGUCCUUUUUUAAAUGUUUUGUGUUUCUCUACAGGUUACAACAGUUGCUUCAGUUGCCUGUUUUAGGUGUUUGCACUUAUUUUAUUUCUUCUUGAAAGAAUUUUUAUUUGCUUUUGUGGUAGAGAUUAUAUGUAAUUUUUUUUCAGUCAUAUAAUGGUGUGCUGUCAACUUAAACACUGACAGGUAAAUAGAAUUGUACACUGUAGUUUGAAUUAUUUAUAAUUGACACACUCUCUCCCUCUCCACUCCUGAAGUAUGCUGCUAUAGAAAAUAGCAGAAUCGGCUUGCUGCUACGAGAGAAGGAAAGAGCGACCACCACUUGCACUGUGUGAAAAGAUAAAAAACAAAUGAUGGCAAGUUCUCAAGUUAACUAAAUGGAAUCAACCAUUACCAGGCAAAUUCUUGCAAAUACCAAAAUACUACUAUGCCUUAUAAAACAAAAUGAAAGCAGGUUAAGAUUUUCUGCUCUGUUUGUAUGUUAAUAGAAAUGGAAAUACUAAGUAUUUUAAUGCUUAGCUCUUGAACAGUAGACCUAAAAGGGUUUUAAGCUAUUUAAAUCUACUUGCUAGUUUUUGCAUAUUUUAUAUAUAUAUAUAUUUAUAUAUAUAUAUAGUGAGAAGUGAAGAAAAUGUAUGGUACUAAGAUUAUGCCUUAUUGAUAAAUAGAUAAACCAAUUUGAAUCCUCUUAGCAUGUUUAAGUAUGUUGAUUGCUUUCUAAUUAAUGAACUUCUCACAGAAAUUUCACUUAGUGAAACCAAUGAUUGUAGCAAACUCAUACUGGAUCAUUUCAGUUACCUUGAACUAAUAGCACAUAAUGGUUUUUUGUUGUUGUUGUUUUUAAUGUAGCCCUUACCUGGAUAUACAUAGUCUGCAAUCACCAAAGUAUAAUAUCUUGUAAGGCUAUAUUUUUUAAAGCAUAUUUUUUCUUGAGCAUUAAAUUAUCCUAAAUGGUAAUAUAUUGUGGAUAAGUCUGGGCUUAUUGGACAUAAUACAUAUUUGGGUUGGUACUGGUUGAAUCCUUCAGUUAACUGCUUUGUUGCUUUUUGCAAGAUUUUUUAUCUUAAACAUGUCAGGCAUCUUAAGUCACCUUUAUACUGUUUUGUUCCUCUGAGUUUCUUUCAGUAUGUUAUACAAAUGCCAGACAUAACAUGUAGCAGCCAUACUUGCAUGGAAACUGACUACACAUACAUAAUACUGCAUUUUAUUGUAAGGUUUUCACAUUAAUACAGCAAUUACCCUGACUAAAUUGAGUUUUGUGAUAUAUGGAAAACUUCAUUGUAAGAGAAUCUUGCAUACAAUGUUGACAUAUUAACAUCCAAAAUAAAGCAUCUGUGUACAAGCUGA